UUAGUGAUUCUCAGCCCUGAUUCACAUUAAAUUUUUAAACACGGGGGAUUCUCUGCCCGGCUGGAAGAAAAUGACUGGAUGGGACAGGGGUCACUAUUUGAAACAUUCCUCUGUGCGGCCAAGGUCGCAAAAUGCUGUCCUCGCAGGGGAACAAAAAGAGUUUGAUUUCCCAUAAUUUGAUGCUGUGAUUUGGUUUCCUCAGGAUGUGAACUGUAGAACAUUCCAGUUACUGGCCUUGAAUGGUUCUGGGAAUAUAAGAAUCCCUGUCUGUCUUUUCAAAUAGUUUUCAUGGAACCUUGUCCUGUUUGAACUUGGCUGAAAAUGGAAGUAAAGAUGCCCUCUUGGGGGCCCAGAGAUGACAGAUGUGGCUCCCCCUGCUGCCCCCACCCCUUCUCCAGACUGUGGGCGGCUCCCCUUCCUGCUUUAGAAUCCUUCAGAUGGAGGAGGCAGUACAGUAGUCACUGUGCCAUCGUGUCUGGCACUGUGCUGGCGUGGUCUGCAGGAUCCCACUUAUGAACUCUCCAGAUUGGGAGCUGUGGCAGGAUAACAGCCCCCAAGACAGCUGUGUCCUAAUCCCCAGAACCUGUGACCACGCUGCCUCACGUGGCAGAAGGGACUCGGCAGGUGUGAUUGAGUGAAGGAUCUUUUUUUUUUUUUUCUUUGAGAUGAAGUUUCGCUCUUGUUGCCCAGGCUGGAGUUCAAUAGCAUGAUCUCAGCUCACUGCAGCCUCUGCCUCCCAGGUUCAAGUGAUUCUCCCACCUCAGCCUCCCGAGUAGCUGGGAUUACAGGUGUCCAGAACCAUACUGGCUAAUUUUUGUAUUUUUAGUAGAGACAGGGUUUCACCAUGUUGACCAGGCUGGUCUCGAACUCCUGACCUCAGGUGAUCCGACCGCCUCGGCCUCCCAAAGUGCUGGGAUUACAGGUGUGAGCCAUCAUGCCUGGCUGAGUUAAGGAUCUUGCAACAGAGAGAUUAUCCUGGAUUGUCUGGGUGGGCCCAGUCCAUUGGGUGAGUCCUUCAAAGGUGGAGACCUUUCCCUGCUGGCCAGAGAGAGGCUGCCUUGCUGGUUUUGGAGAUGGAAGGAGGUACCACUAGUCAAGGAUUGCAAGCAGUCUCUAGAACAGGGAUUCCAACACUCCGGACACAGACCAGUAGUGGUCCAUGGCCUAUUAGGAAGUGGGGUGCACAGCAGGUUAGGGGCCGGCAAGCCAGCGAAGCUUCAUCUGUAUUUAUAGCCACUCCCCGUCGCUGGCGUUACCACCCGAGCUCCGCCUCCUGUCACAUCAGCGGUGGGCAUUAGAUUCUCAUAGCAGCACGAGCCCUAUUGUGAACUGCACACACGAGGGAUGUAGGUUGCACGCUCCUUAUGAGAAUCUGAUGCCUGAUGAUCUGUCACUGUCUCCCGUCACCCCCAGAUGGGGCUGUCUAGUUGCAGGAAAACAAGCUCAGGGCUCCCACUGAGUCUCUGUGAUGGUGAGUUGUAGAAUUAUUUAAUUAUAUGUUACAAUGUAAUAAUAGUAGAAAUAAAGUGCACAAUAAAUGCAAUGCACUUGAAUCGUCCUGAAACCAUCCCUCCCCGACCCCAAUCCAUGGAAAAAUUGUGUUCCGCGAAACCGGUCUCUGGUGCCAAAAAGGUUGGGGACCGCUUCUGGAAAAGCUGGAAAAGGCAAGAAAACGCAUUCUCUCCCUCAGCCUCUGGAAGGAACCAGCACUGUGGGACUAAUUUACAUACUGUAGGGUAAUAAAUUUGUGUUGCUUCGAACCACUAAAUUUAUGGUAAUUUGUUUGCGGCAGCAAUGGAAAACUAAUGCCUGCGUUAUUCCUAUUUUAUGAUGAAGCAGUUAGCAGAGCUGGGAAAACCCUGGCCUGCUGCCUCCAGCGUCCAGCCUUUCCCCCGGCCUUCAGGACCAGCAAGGGCGGGACACCUGCUUGGCGCUGGCGCGCGGCCCCUUUAAGAGCACAGGGUGGGCCUGGCGGCGUCCGCGGUUGCCUGGAGACCGGAGCCGGGUCUGGGACGCCGAGAGCCCGGCAACACCUCAGCCCGAGCCCGGCGAGGUCUCUGGGCUCCUGGAGCGAGGUGAGCGCCCCAGGCCGCGGUCCUGCCUACGCCGGGACAGCCAUGGCGACUGGGUCCUGCUCCUUCCCGGCCGGACUGACGCGGCCUCCCAGGACCCGAGCACGUGCGUGAUGGGCGAGGAGGGCCUAGGCCGGGCAGACCAGUGCAGGGAGCCGAUUCUUCUCGGCUCACCGUAGACACAGGAGAGAGAUGGCCUCUCCUUAAGCCCAGGAGAACAGAGGAAACAUUAGGAAACGCACUGAGAAACGAAAUUGGCUUGAUUUGUAGUUCACUUAUUUGUAGAUCACUGACAGAAGACCGAAAAGCUCGUAGUAAAGGCCCCUCUAAAUUUAGAGAGAGGUGGCAUCUCACUACGUGGCCUAGGCUGAUCUCCCUCUCCUGGACUCACAUGAUCCUCCCACCUUGGCCCUUCAACGUGCUGAGAUCGCAGGUGUGAGCCACCACACCCGGCCCUGAUAAAACUCAUCAGUGCUUUGAAACAAGCAGCUCUGAACCAAAGAAAUCAUUUGAUUCAAGUAACCAUUGGAUCUUCCCAAGGCAAUGGUGAAAGAAAAGAAAAAAGCAGACAAAAAAGGGGAGAAGUCUGCCCGCUCUCCCUCAUCUCUCUCUGAUAAUCUAGACUUUUCCAAACAAGAUGGCAACACCACUAGGCAAGAGAUGUCCCCAGCUGGUGUCCCAUUGCUGGGAAUGCAGCUCAACGAAGUGAAACCCAAAAAAGACCGCCAAAACGUUCAGCAGAACGAAGAUGCCAGCCAAUACGAAGAGUCCAUUCUGACCAAACUCAUAGUGGAAAGCUAUGAAGGGGAAAAGGUUCGUGGGCUGUAUGAGGGAGAAGGCUUCGCAGCCUUUCAAGGCGGUUGUACCUAUCGUGGUAUGUUUUCAGAAGGACUCAUGCAUGGACAGGGGACUUAUAUUUGGGCCGAUGGAUUAAAAUAUGAGGGCGACUUUGUGAAGAAUGUCCCGAUGAACCACGGCGUGUACACGUGGCCGGACGGCAGCAUGUAUGAAGGCGAAGUGGUCAACGGCAUGAGGAACGGAUUCGGGAUGUUCAAGUGCAGCACCCAGCCUGUGUCCUACAUCGGCCACUGGUGCAAUGGCAAGCGGCACGGGAAGGGCUCCAUUUAUUACAAUCAAGAGGGUACGUGUUGGUACGAGGGAGACUGGGUACAAAACAUCAAAAAGGGCUGGGGAAUAAGAUGUUAUAAAUCUGGAAAUAUAUACGAAGGCCAGUGGGAAGACAACAUGCGCCACGGGGAGGGGAGGAUGAGGUGGCUGACCACCAACGAAGAGUACACCGGGCGGUGGGAGAGGGGCAUCCAGAAUGGCUUUGGAACACACACAUGGUUUCUAAAGAGAAUCCGCAGUUCCCAGUAUCCUUUGAGAAAUGAAUACAUAGGGGAGUUUGUAAAUGGAUAUCGUCACGGACGUGGCAAGUUUUAUUAUGCCAGUGGAGCCAUGUAUGAUGGAGAAUGGGUUUCCAAUAAGAAACAUGGCAUGUUUUUCUGUCUGCAGGGCCGAUUAACUUUCAAGAACGGGCGUGUGUACGAAGGCGCAUUCUCCAAUGACCACAUAGCUGGGUUUCCGGAUCUUGAAGUUGAAUUCAUCAGCUGCCUGGACCUGUCUUCAGGAGUUGCCCCAAGACUGUCCAGGAGCGCCGAACUGAUCAGAAAGCUUGAUGGCAGUGAAAGUCAUUCUGUGUUGGGAUCGAGCAUUGAGCUGGAUCUAAAUUUGCUCCUGGACAUGUACCCUGAGACAGUCCAACCUGAAGAAAAGAAGCAGGUGGAAUAUGCCGUCUUAAGAAAUAUUACAGAAUUAAGAAGAAUUUACAGCUUUUACAGCAGCCUGGGAUGCGGCCACUCUCUGGAUAAUACCUUUCUGAUGACAAAGCUUCACUUCUGGAGAUUUCUAAAAGAUUGCAAAUUUCAUCACCACAAACUAACUCUUGCUGAUAUGGACAGGAUAUUAAGUGCCAAUAAUGACAUACCAGUUGAAGAAAUCCAUUCUCCAUUUACAACAAUACUUUUGAGAACAUUUUUGAAUUACCUCCUGCAUUUGGCGUACCACAUUUAUCAUGAAGAAUUCCAGCAAUUUAUUCCGUGAGCAACAGCGGACGCUCUACUCUAUGAGUUACAUGAAUAAGUGCUGGGAGAUUUAUCUCGCUUACUGCAGACCCAGUGCAGCGCCUCCCCACGAGCCUA